ACACUCAUUUUAGCCAGUGUCCAGGCUAUCAGCAGAGAAAGACAGGUGGGCAGCAUGGCUCCGGGCGAAAAGGAAAGCGGGGAGGGCCCAGCCAAGAGCGCCCUCCGGAAGAUACGCACAGCCACCCUGGUCAUCAGCUUGGCCCGAGGUUGGCAGCAGUGGGCGAAUGAGAACAGCAUCAGGCAGGCCCAGGAGCCUACAGGCUGGCUGCCGGGAGGGACCCAGGACUCACCUCAAGCUCCUAAACCAAUCACACCCCCUACUUCACACCAGAAAGCUCAGAGUGCCCCAAAGUCGCCACCCCGCCUGCCAGAAGGACAUGGAGAUGGACAAAGCUCAGAGAAAGCCCCUGAGGUUUCUCACAUCAAAAAGAAAGAGGUGUCCAAAACGGUGGUCAGCAAGACUUAUGAGAGAGGAGGGGACGUGAGCCACCUCAGCCACAGGUACGAGAGGGAUGCUGGUGUGCUUGAACCUGGGCAGCCAGAGAAUGACAUUGACAGAAUCCUCCACAGCCACGGCUCCCCAACGCGGAGGAGAAAAUGUGCCAACCUGGUGUCUGAGCUAACCAAGGGCUGGAGAGUGAUGGAGCAGGAGGAGCCCACAUGGAGGAGUGACAGCGUAGACACAGAGGACAGCGGCUAUGGAGGAGAGGCUGAGGAGAGGCCCGAGCAGGAUGGAGUGCAGGUGGCUGUGGUCAGGAUCAAGCGCCCCUUGCCCUCCCAGGUAAACAGAUUUACAGAGAAACUCAACUGCAAAGCCCAACAGAAAUAUAGCCCAGUGGGCAACUUGAAAGGGAGAUGGCAGCAGUGGGCUGAUGAACACAUACAAUCCCAGAAGCUCAAUCCUUUCAGUGAAGAGUUUGAUUACGAGCUGGCCAUGUCCACCCGCCUACACAAAGGAGAUGAGGGCUAUGGCCGCCCCAAAGAAGGAACCAAAACUGCUGAAAGGGCCAAGCGUGCUGAGGAGCACAUCUACAGGGAAAUGAUGGACAUGUGCUUCAUUAUCUGCACAAUGGCUCGCCACAGACGAGAUGGCAAGAUCCAGGUUACUUUUGGAGAUCUCUUUGACAGAUACGUUCGUAUUUCAGAUAAAGUAGUGGGCAUUCUCAUGCGUGCCAGGAAACAUGGACUGGUAGACUUUGAAGGAGAGAUGCUAUGGCAAGGCCGAGAUGACCAUGUUGUGAUUACGCUACUCAAGUGAACCUUCAAAAACAAAAGCCAAAUUUGGCCCACUAUGGUCUUAAUGCUAAAUGCUCAUGUAGGUAAAAUGAAAAUGCAAACUCUCUGUAAUAAGUUAGUAAAUAUUAAACAAUUUUUACAUAAACGACUUUCUGGCAUUCUAUUUCUAUCUAGAAUGAGGAAUUUUGGAGAUUUUGAGAAGGCACAAAGCAUUUCAGAAAGCACAUAGAAUGUUAAUGUAUAAUAAUAGUAUUAAUAGUUGAAAUUCCACAGGGUGUUUUUGUUUUUGUUUUGAGACAGAUUCUCUUUAUGUCACCAAAGCUGGUCUUUUAACUCCUGGCCUCAAGUGAUCCUCUCACCUCAGCCUCCCAAGUAGCUGGGAUUAUAGGCAUGAGCAACAGCACCCAGCCACUUGUAUAUUUUAGGCAAAAUAUUUAGCUAGUCAUUGUAGAAACUACUAUAGAUUUUUAAUUAAACAUUACAUCUAAGAAGAAUGCUGACUUGAGAUAAAUAUCAGUAGAACAUAUAAUAAUGUGUCUUUAUUUGGAAAAAAGAAAAUACCAUUAAGUUUGGUAAAACUAAACUUAAAAUUUUUUCAGAAGCUUGACUUUGUAUUAUUGUUUAUAUCAUAGCAUCACUUACAAAACAAGCACAUAUAUAAAAAGUUGUCAAGAUGUUGCUGAAAUUGUUGAAGUUCCUCUGUGGGCUUGGAUUCUAACAGGUUUCCAGUAAGAGUUCACCUUCCUCUUGUUUGAUUUCAGCAAAUCACAUAAAAACAGACACUUCCUGUCUUAGUACCAACAAAGGAAGGCACACCCUCACUAAAAGUAGAGCAGAGGUGAGAGAUUCAGAUUUACUUGCCUUUGUAGGACUUCUUGGAGAAGUUUAUUGUUUCAUUACAUGUCAGCAUAUAACGAGUCAAGCUGCUUGCAUUAACAUCAAUGCAAUGAUAUGUAUUUCUCCAACAAUGGAGAAAUACAGAAAAUCUAUGAAGUGGAAUGUUCAGUAUUAGAAAAAUCCCAUAGAAUCAUUGGUGAAUUAAAAACAGAUUUGAGACAGUUUAAUGUUCCUCAUACUGUAACAAAGAAAACUUUAUGAAAUGUUUAAGUCAUAAAACUGCAAUAUUAGUUCUGCCAAAGUAAAAAAUAUACAAUGAUGAUGGCAAGGAGAAAAUCAUUGGACAUUAAUGUGCCUAUGUGAUCUUAAAAACAAAUGGAAUGGAAUGUGAGAUUGCAAUUCUUACUGGAUUCAAUGAAAUUACUAAAAUGCAUUGAUAGUAUAGCACUUUGGUGUUAAAUGUAAAAAUUAAUGUCUAAAUAUGAUACCUCAAAAUAAUAGGUAUUAGACUGCUAUAAGAAUUAUAUUUGUUUUCAUGUAUGAGUCUCUUUCAAACUGAAGGUUCUGGUAUCUUAAGAAAGUAUGCGUAUUUUGUUUCCAUACCGUAUUUAUAAAGCUAUAAGUUAAUGACCAAUAUUUCUAAGUAGGAUUUCAUGUAAGAUGCACACUUCUAUUACAAGUGAAACCUACGCCAAAUGUUAAAGACAAAUAGCAUAAGAAUAAAAGAUGUUUUCUUGUA